GUCUGUGCUCCCGGCGCUGACGUGUCUGGGCGGUCGGCUUCCACUCCUUCAGGCGUCGGCAGCCACUAGUCGUGGCGAGAGGGGCGGGGUGGCCGGGGCUGGCGCUCCACUUGGCCCCCGCUCCCGGCCCGCCCCGCCGCCGCGGCCCCCCGGAUGAGGGUAUAUAUUCGGAGCGAGCGCGGGACGCCGAUGAGUGGCCGCGCGGAAGGAGCUGGAGACGGUCGUAGCUGCGGUCGCGCCGAGAAAGAAGGAUGGUAUUGGAGGGCUGAGCACACGUAUGCUGAACAUAUGGCUGCUUGAACUUUGGCCUGUCGCUGUGCUACACUUACUUCUACAUGGUUUAUGAAAUCUGAAAUCAGGUUUACAGGUACAUACAUUACACCCCUAUUUCUACAAAGCUUGGCUAUUAGAGCAUUAUGAACAUUAAUGACCUCAAACUCACGUUGUCCAAAGCUGGGCAAGAGCACCUACUACGUUUCUGGAAUGAGCUUGAAGAAGCCCAACAGGUAGAACUUUAUGCAGAGCUCCAGGCCAUGAACUUUGAGGAGCUGAACUUCUUUUUCCAAAAGGCCAUUGAAGGUUUUAACCAGUCUUCUCACCAAAAGAAUGUGGAUGCACGAAUGGAACCUGUGCCUCGAGAGGUAUUAGGCAGUGCUACAAGGGAUCAAGAUCAGCUCCAGGCCUGGGAAAGUGAAGGACUUUUCCAGAUUUCUCAGAAUAAAGUAGCAGUUCUUCUUCUAGCUGGUGGGCAGGGGACAAGACUCGGCGUUGCAUAUCCUAAGGGGAUGUAUGAUGUUGGUUUGCCAUCCCGUAAGACACUUUUUCAGAUUCAAGCAGAGCGUAUCCUGAAGCUACAGCAGGUUGCUGAAAAAUAUUAUGGCAACAAAUGCAUUAUUCCAUGGUAUAUAAUGACCAGUGGCAGAACAAUGGAAUCUACAAAGGAGUUCUUCACCAAGCACAAGUACUUUGGUUUAAAAAAAGAGAAUGUAAUCUUUUUUCAGCAAGGAAUGCUCCCCGCCAUGAGUUUUGAUGGGAAAAUUAUUUUGGAAGAGAAGAACAAAGUUUCUAUGGCUCCAGAUGGGAAUGGUGGUCUUUAUCGGGCACUUGCAGCCCAGAAUAUUGUGGAGGAUAUGGAGCAAAGAGGCAUUUGGAGCAUUCAUGUCUAUUGUGUUGACAACAUAUUAGUAAAAGUGGCAGACCCACGGUUCAUUGGAUUUUGCAUUCAGAAAGGAGCAGACUGUGGAGCAAAGGUGGUAGAGAAAACGAACCCUACAGAACCAGUUGGAGUGGUUUGCCGAGUGGAUGGAGUUUACCAGGUGGUAGAAUAUAGUGAGAUUUCCCUGGCAACAGCUCAAAAACGAAGCUCAGACGGACGACUGCUGUUCAAUGCGGGGAACAUUGCCAACCAUUUCUUCACUGUACCAUUUCUGAGAGAUGUUGUCAAUGUUUAUGAACCUCAGUUGCAGCACCAUGUGGCUCAAAAGAAGAUUCCUUAUGUGGAUACCCAAGGACAGUUAAUUAAGCCAGACAAACCCAAUGGAAUAAAGAUGGAAAAAUUUGUCUUUGACAUCUUCCAGUUUGCAAAGAAGUUUGUGGUAUAUGAAGUAUUGCGAGAAGAUGAGUUUUCCCCACUAAAGAAUGCUGAUAGUCAGAAUGGGAAAGACAACCCUACUACUGCAAGGCAUGCUUUGAUGUCCCUUCAUCAUUGCUGGGUCCUCAAUGCAGGGGGCCAUUUCAUAGAUGAAAAUGGCUCUCGCCUUCCAGCAAUUCCCCGUGCUACAAAUGGGAAGUCAGAGACCAUCACAGCUGAUGUCAAUCACAACUUGAAGGAUGCCAAUGAUGUACCAAUCCAAUGUGAAAUCUCUCCUCUUAUCUCCUAUGCUGGAGAAGGAUUAGAAAGUUAUGUGGCAGAUAAAGAAUUCCAUGCACCUCUAAUCAUCGAUGAGAAUGGAGUUCAUGAGCUGGUGAAAAAUGGUAUUUGAACCAGAUACCAAGUUUUGUUUGCCACGAUAGGAAUAGCUUUUAUUUUUGAUAGACCAACUGUGAACCUACAAGACGUCUUGGACAACUGAAGUUUAAAUAUCCACAGGGUUUUAUUUUGCUUGUUGAACUCUUAGAGCUAUUGCAAACUUCCCAAGAUCCAGAUGACUGAAUUUCAGAUAGCAUUUUUAUGAUUCCCAACUCAUUGAAGGUCUUAUUUAUAUAAUUUUUUCCAAGCCAAGGAGACCAUUGGCCAUCCAGGAAAUUUCGUACAGCUGAAAUAUAGGCAGGAUGUUCAACAUCAGUUUACUUGCAGCUGGAAGCAUUUGUUUUUGAAGUUGUACAUAGUAAUAAUAUGUCAUUGUACAUGUUGAAAGGUUUCUAUGGUACUAAAAGUUUGUUUUAUUUUAUCAAACAUUAAGCUUUUUUAAGAAAAUAAUUGGGCAGUGAAAUAAAUGUAUCUUCUUGUCUCUGGAGUGUCAUUUGUACUUGAAGAAAUUAUUUCAUUGAGAAAAUAUGAAACUUGGGAGAAACUUUAAGAUAAUGCAUAAAAACAAAUUGAUGCUUCAGUGAGGUUGCAGAGUCAUAGAACUUCUUUCAGUGAAUAUCUAACUUUGGGCUUUAUCUUCUUAUCACUUUAUAAUAGUAGCUCUCACCCAAAGAUUAUUUUGUCCUCCACCCAAAGGGGCAUUUGGCAAUGUCUGGAGAUAUUUUUGGUUGUGACAAGUGGGAAAGUGAAGUGGUACCACUGGCAUCUAAUAGGGAUUAGGGAUGUCACUAAACAUCCUACAAUGCACAGGAUGGUCUCCUACGACAAAGAGUUAUCUGGCCUAAAGUGUCAAUGGUGUCAAGGUCGAGAAGCCUUGUUUCAAAUUAUUCAUUUACUCUGUUUUGCCCAAAUAUUUGGUGGCACUUAGGAAUUCAAAAGAAUGUAGUUUCUGAAUUUUCUCUGGUAGGCUAUUCCAGUUUUUUGUUAUUGUUGUUGUUAUUUUAGAGGAUUAAAAAAAUAAAAAGACAAAGGUGGUUCUUUAAAUAUGGGCCAUAGAUCAUUGGUCAUUAGUAAGGGUUCUCUGUGUCUAAAAUGCUGUUUGCAUGAAAAGACUGAGCUUUAUAAAUGCAUCUUAAAUAAUAUUUAAGUAUUGACCAAAAGUAUAAAAAGGAACAUCUGGAUAAAUGAUUCUAAAAAUUAUAUCUAGAAAAGAGAUGAAUAAAUUUCAUUUUCCGCUAACAAGUUGUCACAAGAUAGGAUGUCAUUCAUGGGGUGGGUCUUUUGUUUAAGGAUCACUUUUUUUUUUUUUUGAAGAGCAUGUGAUGUUCAUAUCCAUCAAUCUUACCUAUUUUUUUUUUAACUAAGGCCUAAAUCAUUCAUUUAGCAUAUUUUCUAUUUUAUUUCAAUAACAGCUCAAUUUUGCUAUUGUUAUCUAUUCCAGUUUUCAAAAAGAUUAGUGAAGUUUGACUUCUCAUUGAAAUGAGCUCCAAAUGGGUUGUAAGAAUGGAAUUGCAGAGUCUUUAGCUCCUGAAUGCCAAAAACUGAUACUAAUGGUAUGAUCCGUUUCUUUUUUUCUUGAACCUUGCUAUUUCCUCUGCUAUUUCCACCUGCUAUUUAUUCUUCUCCUGUUGUAAGAAAAUACUAGUGAUGCUAGGAAAAGGGAAGAAUGGAAAUGGGAUUGUGUAGUGGUUUUGUUGGAGAGGAGCGAUGGCUGGGGAACAUUGGGUAGUUAAGAGCAAACUCUGAGAGCCUCUGAGCCAUGAAAUGAUAAGGUGAUAGCAUUAUGUAUUUUUAUGAGUUCUUGUUAAAUAAUUGUUAUAAUUCAGAAAAUACAGAAUUGGGUAAAAUGUUUAUGAAAAUAAAAGCUAGAAUAAUUUGGCAGUAACAGUA